AUGAGCAGCAAUUCAUCCCUGCUGGUGGCUGUGCAGCUGUGCUACGCGAACGUGAAUGGGUCCUGUGUGAAAAUCCCCUUCUCGCCGGGAUCCCGGGUGAUUCUGUACAUAGUGUUUGGCUUUGGGGCUGUGCUGGCUGUGUUUGGAAACCUCCUGGUGAUGAUUUCAAUCCUCCAUUUCAAGCAGCUGCACUCUCCGACCAAUUUUCUCGUUGCCUCUCUGGCCUGCGCUGAUUUCUUGGUGGGUGUGACUGUGAUGCCCUUCAGCAUGGUCAGGACGGUGGAGAGCUGCUGGUAUUUUGGGAGGAGUUUUUGUACUUUCCACACCUGCUGUGAUGUGGCAUUUUGUUACUCUUCUCUCUUUCACUUGUGCUUCAUCUCCAUCGACAGGUACAUUGCGGUUACUGACCCCCUGGUCUAUCCUACCAAGUUCACCGUAUCUGUGUCAGGAAUUUGCAUCAGCGUGUCCUGGAUCCUGCCCCUCAUGUACAGCGGUGCUGUGUUCUACACAGGUGUCUAUGACGAUGGGCUGGAGGAAUUAUCUGAUGCCCUAAACUGUAUAGGAGGUUGUCAGACCGUUGUAAAUCAAAACUGGGUGUUGACAGAUUUUCUAUCCUUCUUUAUACCUACCUUUAUUAUGAUAAUUCUGUAUGGUAACAUAUUUCUUGUGGCUAGACGACAGGCGAAAAAGAUAGAAAAUACUGGUAGCAAGACAGAAUCAUCCUCAGAGAGUUACAAAGCCAGAGUGGCCAGGAGAGAGAGAAAAGCAGCUAAAACCCUGGGGGUCACAGUGGUAGCAUUUAUGAUUUCAUGGUUACCAUAUAGCAUUGAUUCAUUAAUUGAUGCCUUUAUGGGCUUUAUAACCCCUGCCUGUAUUUAUGAGAUUUGCUGUUGGUGUGCUUAUUAUAACUCAGCCAUGAAUCCUUUGAUUUAUGCUUUAUUUUACCCAUGGUUUAGGAAAGCAAUAAAAGUUAUUGUAACUGGUCAGGUUUUAAAGAACAGUUCAGCAACCAUGAAUUUGUUUUCUGAACAUAUAUAA